ACGCCCAGCUCUGGGUGCUCCAGCUGGGCCACAGCCUGGUCCUGCCGCUGCGCCCGCCCGCCAUGGUGUCCCGGGACCAGGCUCACCUGGGCCCCAAGUAUGUGGGCCUCUGGGACUUCAAGUCCCGGACGGACGAGGAGCUGAGCUUCCGCGCGGGGGACGUCUUCCACGUGGCCAGGAAGGAGGAGCAGUGGUGGUGGGCCACGCUGCUGGACGAGGCGGGUGGGGCCGUGGCCCAGGGCUAUGUGCCCCACAACUACCUGGCCGAGAGGGAGACGGUGGAGUCGGAACCGUGGUUCUUUGGCUGCAUCUCCCGCUCGGAAGCUGUGCGUCGGCUGCAGGCCGAGGGCAACGCCACGGGCGCCUUCCUGAUCAGGGUCAGCGAGAAGCCGAGUGCCGACUACGUCCUGUCGGUGCGGGACACGCAGGCUGUGCGGCACUACAAGAUCUGGCGGCGUGCCGGGGGCCGGCUGCACCUGAACGAGGCGGUGUCCUUCCUCAGCCUGCCCGAGCUUGUGAACUACCACAGGGCCCAGAGCCUGUCCCACGGCCUGCGGCUGGCCGCGCCCUGCCGGAAGCACGAGCCUGAGCCCCUGCCCCAUUGGGAUGACUGGGAGAGGCCGAGGGAGGAGUUCACGCUCUGCAGGAAGCUGGGGUCCGGCUACUUUGGGGAGGUCUUCGAGGGGCUCUGGAAAGACCGGGUCCAGGUGGCCAUUAAGGUGAUUUCUCGAGACAACCUCCUGCACCAGCAGAUGCUGCAGUCGGAGAUCCAGGCCAUGAAGAAGCUGCGGCACAAACACAUCCUGGCGCUGUACGCCGUGGUGUCCGUGGGGGACCCCGUGUACAUCAUCACGGAGCUCAUGGCCAAGGGCAGCCUGCUGGAGCUGCUCCGCGACUCUGAUGAGAAAGUCCUGCCCGUUUCGGAGCUGCUGGACAUCGCCUGGCAGGUGGCUGAGGGCAUGUGUUACCUGGAGUCGCAGAAUUACAUCCACCGGGACCUGGCCGCCAGGAACAUCCUCGUCGGGGAAAACACCCUCUGCAAAGUUGGGGACUUCGGGUUAGCCAGGCUUAUCAAGGAGGACGUCUACCUCUCCCAUGACCACAAUAUCCCCUACAAGUGGACGGCCCCUGAAGCGCUCUCCCGAGGCCAUUACUCCACCAAAUCCGACGUCUGGUCCUUUGGGAUUCUCCUGCAUGAGAUGUUCAGCAGGGGUCAGGUGCCCUACCCAGGCAUGUCCAACCAUGAGGCCUUCCUGAGGGUGGACGCCGGCUACCGCAUGCCCUGCCCUCUGGAGUGCCCGCCCAGCGUGCACAAGCUGAUGCUGACAUGCUGGUGCAGGGACCCCGAGCAGAGACCCUGCUUCAAGGCCCUGCGGGAGAGGCUCUCCAGCUUCACCAGCUACGAGAACCCGACCUGAGCUGCUGUGGAGCGGGCAUGGCCGGGCCCUGCUGAGGAGGGGCCUGGGCAGAGGGCCUGGACCUGGGAUCAAGGCCCACGCGCUUCCCUGGGGUUUACUGAGGUGAUGGGUGCAGGAAAGGUUCACAAAUGUGGAGUGUCUGCGUCCAAUACACGCGUGUGCUCCUCUCCUUACUCCAUCGUGUGUGCCUUGGGUCUCAGCUGCUGACACGCAGCCUGCUCUGGAGCCUGCAGAUGAGAUCCGGGAGACUGACACGAAGCCAGCAGAGGUCAGAGGGGACUCUGACCACAGCCCGCUCUCUGGCUGUCUGUCUGCAGUGCCCGGCUGAGGGUGGGAGGCAAACACGCCUUGUUCCUGCUCUUCCCAGUUCAGCUUGGUGGGAGAAAGUCAUUCGCGUGGCUCGGGACGCUCAUGUAAAUUUGGUUUUGGUGCUCAAGGGUUCUUUCCUCCCAGGGGCAGGUGUUUCUUUCCUGUUUGUCUUGUGUCUUGAGAGCUUGGCCUUAUGACCAGUGAGAACUCUCUCCCUGGUCUCUGCCAGCCCAAGCAUCACUGCCCGAGGCGCCAGCUCAGUUUCACCGUCCACGUCCACAAGGGGCUUUUCCCACCUUCACCUUUGUCGCUGGGUCAGUGCUGGAAAGCGCCCCUCACUCCUGCGCUGACAAGGGCCCUUCUCUACUGUCUGUGGGGUGGUUCCGGGCUGGGGGGGCUGCCUCCUUUGCACCUGAUUUUGAAGGUGUCUCUUUCAUCCAUGGUUAAGUCAUAAAAAGCUUAUUGGUUUUGGUUUUGACUCACCUGAAAGUUUUUUUGGUUUAAAAGAAGAAUAGGCGGGGCACGGUGGCUCAUGCCUGUAAUCCCAGCACUUUGGGAGGCUGAGGCAGGUGGAUCACGAGGUCAGGAGAUCGACACCAUCCUGGCUAACACGGUGAAACCCCGUCUCUACUAAAAAAUACAAAAAAUUAGCUGGGUGUGGUGGUGGGGGUGGGCGCCUGUAGUCCCAGCUACGUGGGAGGCUGAGGCAGCAGACUGGUGUGAACCCGGGAGGUGGAGCUUGCAGUGAGCCGAGAUCGCGCCACUGCACUCCAGCCUGGGCGACAGAGCGAGACUCCAUCUCAAAAAAAAAAAAAAAAAAAAGAAAGAAAGAAAAAUAAUUUUGGGAGUUUCUGGAAAGGUACUAGGAUUUCUCAAAAGGAUUUGUCUUCUGCCUUGUGAAAGACAGAUGUCAGACUAAUCAGGCUUAUCCGAUGUGCUACAUGAGAUGGAAAGCGUGUGAAAUAGUAAGUCACACUAAGUCUUCUGGAGGUUCUAUUUACGGGUUUGGUUUUGAUAUGAAUGUUGCAGAAACUCUAUAAAAUUCCUAGAAAUCUGAUACGUUAUCCUAUGAUAUAUAUCCUAUCUCACAUGCUAUUCCUAGAAAUCUGGUGCAAUGUUAUCAGUCAUAAUUUUGGUUAUUACAUUAAAAUGCUGCAUGCCACAGAAAUAACCAAGUUUCCUUGCCAACCGUGUCACGAAUAUAAUAAACUCUCAUCAGAUCCUGA